AUCUGCUCUGACUUCCCCAGGACGUGUCUGUGCUCCUGUGUGUGACCAGGGUUGAAAAAGUCGCACUGAGAUGUCCUGCCAGCAAAACCAGCAGCAGUGCCAGCCCCCUCCCAAGUGCCCCCCAAAAUGCCCACCCAAGUGUCCUCCAAAGUGCCGACCUCAGUGCCCAGCCCCAUGCCCACCUCCAGUCUCUUCCUGCUGUGGUCCCAGCUCUGGGGGCUGCUGCGGCUCCAGCUCUGGGGGCUGCUGCAGCUCUGGGGGUGGCGGCUGCUGCCUGAGCCACCACAGGCCCCGUCUCUUCCACCGGCACCGGCACCAGAGCCCCGAUUGUUGUGAGUGUGAACCUUCUGGGGGCUCUGGCUGCUGCCACAGCUCUGGGGACUGCUGCUGACCAGACCUCGAACAUCACAGAGCAACCCUUAUGGAGAAACUUGCAACCAGGACCUGUCCCAGAGUGAUGCUUCUCCUGCCCCUUUUUCUCCUUUCCUUGGGCUGACACACCUUGUGAGGUGUUUUGUCUGUUGUCAUGGCCCAAGAGCCCAUCCUGGAUCCUGAUCUUACCUUCCCACUUUACCUCAUACAACAAUAAAGCUCUUUUGCCUCUUCGUGAA